GAGGGGGGGAAAUGGAAGGUUUAAUUUUAGAGUAAUUUAUUUUUAAUGAAGUAAAAUGGUUUUGAUUUAGUGUCAUGGACCUGUUAAUAACAAAGACAAUUACUUUGUGGUUCUUCAAGGUCAAUGUCUUUCAACACCGUCAGCUUUUUCUGUUGUAAAAUGUGAAAAAUACCACAUAUCUUCUACCUACCUCACAGGGAUGUUGUGAGGGUUGAUAAGGACAAAUGCUACAAAGCUCAGUGAUUUUUAAAUUACAUUUGUGGUAGUAGUAGUUUCUAGAAGAAUUAUUUUGUCAACUUACGGUGACACAGUUUCUCAGAUUUUAAAUUUUUUUAUACAUUCUUCUACUUGACCAGUCUUACUUAAGGAUGGUGCCAUAUAUAUUGGAAAGAUGACUGUCUGACUUACAUUUACUUCCUGAAUCUGUUAAUUUCUGAAUUUCUGAUGUGAAAGUAUUUCUAUAAGUUUUUUUUGUUUUUUAAUUUUUACUCUUCAGGUUGGUCACAAGAAUCUGGGCUUAUUUAUUUCCAUAUGAUUUCUUAUAGUUUAGUUUAGGAAAUAGCAGUGUUAGGCUGUUAGAAAACACUGAAAAUUCUAGCCUGGUUCGUGUUCAUGGAAGAGGGGAUUGAAGGAUUAGAAUUGGGGCCAGUCAUACUACAUCCUGCCAUUUCCACAGUCUAUUCAGCCUAGUGAUUCUAGUCUUCAAAAGAAAUUGUGAACAUAUUUACCUUUUCUGAGUAUAUGUUGAAAGGGGAGUUUAAAUACUUUCAUGAUUUAGUCAUAUGUUCUUAUUAAAAGGACAGAAUCUUUUUUUAGUGCCUUUGGCCUAAUAAAGCUGUAAAAACCUUUGUUUGUUGGCUUCAACUUGAAGAAGCUUGAUUUCAUGGUCAGAUUUAGGAAUACAUGUAAACUAAACAUUUUGACCAUUUUCUGAAGAGAGGAAGCUAACUGAAAGGUGACUCUGGAGCUGAGGAUUGUUUAGAACCACCAUUUCAUUUAUAUUGUUCAUCUAAGUGAUUAUAAUUGGUUUUAGCAGGUGAGAAUAUUCAGUCUCUUUCCAUUUGUAUAUAUUAUUUUCAUGCCUGUCUCUGAUAAAGGAUAUACUUGGCCCCAGGAGAGGAAAUAUUUUAAAUCAAUUAACCUGUUACACCUUUUCCUUGUAAACUAUUAACCUUGGAGAAAGCCAAAUGUUCUCUAAGUGUUUGUUCUUAUGGCAUGAGACUUCAGUUUUGCCUUAAAAUAUGGAACCCAGUGCUAUGUGCUGGGCAGAAGUGGAAUAGUAUUUCUAACUCCUGUGAUACAAAGAUUGAAACAACACUAUUGGAGGAGUCGAGAUCAAAGAAGACGGAGAUGACACUGACAUGAUACAACUGCCAGCUUUCCAGCAUCAUGCUUUUUUUCCUUCAAUUUGGAUAACCUGCUUUAAUAGUUUCAAUCAAUAUACUCUUACAUAUGCCUUACUGGGAUAUUCAAGCUCAACGUUUAAAGAAGUAAAAAAAACAAAAAACUACAACACAAAAACUCUGCUGAGCCCACAAUGAUGCAUUAUUUCUCUAUGGCCUUGAAAAGACAGUAGUGGGGAAAAAAAGUACCAUUUUACCAUGUGCCUCAAGUUUGUAAUACUGGUUGCUUAAACACCCUUCCCUUCCACGGUGGGAUUUUCUCUUCACUUUCCCUUGGGAGUCUCAAAUGAAUAAGUUACAGUUUGACAGCAGCAGCAGAGCAUAAGAUUUUAUGAAUGUGAAACCAUUAUGAUCUUUUUAUUUACUUAGAAAAUUUAAGUGUGUGAUAAUCUUUUUAAUAGUUCAUUUUUCUACAUCUAUUUCUGAUUUCAUGUUGCAACUAUGUCAUGCAAAAAGACAGUAGAUAUUGUAAGAUUGUCUUCAACAGUUGAAAUUCAGGCUUGCCUUUUUACAGUAGAUUUCAUUUAUAGUUUAUACAGAUAAAUGAGAACUAAUAUAAAAUAGUAAUUUUGUUAUGGCAUUAUGGUAUAUUUUAAAUUCAUCAAGCUCAUCUGUAUGUGUCUUUUUGUCCUUUUACUACUGAGAGGAUUGGGGCUGGGAUCAUGGCAGCCUGCUCUGAUGUAUUUCUCUCCACUCUAUUUUAUUAUUUUUUUAAAGAGUUCUAACUUAAAUACGUGGACCAGCUAUUGGAUAACUUUAAUUCAUAUAUUUAUCAUUCUUUCUAUUCACUUUGCCACAUACACACCAUGUGAUGAUUUUAAACCCGAUUUCUGUAUAGAGAAUGUUAAAAGGAUGGCGUUUUUCAGAGGUUCCAAAUAGGUAGACAUUGACAAUAUAGUUGCACAGUAUAUGGAAUACGUAUAUGUAUAGACAUAUAUACACACAUAUACAUACAGAUAUACAUAUAUAUUUCUAUGUAUACACAUAUACAUAUAUCAUAUAUGUACACAUAUGCAUAUUGCAUAUACUGUGCAAUAUAUAUAUACACACACAAUUUCCCAGUUCGUAUUUUUCAUUAUGUCAUGUACCUUAUUGAUAGCUAUUAUUAUAUGGCUUAUGCAUACUGAUUUGAAAUAAACAAUUUUACUUAGAAAACUAGUAGUCCAUACUUUUGGAACAAAGUCACAAACAAAUUGAAUUUGAUUAGACUUUAAACUACAGAAUGUCAAGGGAAUAAAGGAAAAAAACAUCAGCAGUUGGUGCAUGAUCUGUUUCUAAUAGGCUCUAAGAGUUCCUGGAAUUUCAGUUAGCUUAGGUGUGUUUCUGUAACUUAAGGAAUUUAAAAAGUUUAAAAAAUCCUGAAAUUUGAAUUGACCAGUAGUAUGUUAUUGAUAAUAAUAUCAAGAAUAUUUGAUUCUUAGUCCCAGCAAGAAGAUUGUGUUUUGGAAUACCUGGAUGAAAAGUAGACCAAGAAUGUAACCACUUUGCUCUUUCUUUGUUCCCCUUUCCCAUUCCAGGGAGCUCUGGGCUCUGUUCUACUUAUUCGUAUUGGCAGGAAGAGACCAGCUGUGUAUUUUAUAGCUAAUAUAGAAUACUGGAAGGUUGUAACUUUAUUGGUUUGUUGGCAUCCAAAGCUGUUGGGGUUGAUGGUGCUGAAAAAAAGGAAGACUACAAUGAAACAGCUCCAAUGCUGGAGCAGGCGAUUUCACCUAAACCUCAAAGUCAGAAAAAAAAUGAAGCUGACAUUAGCAGUUCUGCCAACACUCAGAAACCUGCACUGUUAUCCUCAACUUUGUCUUCAGGGAAGGCUCGCAGCAAGAAAUGCAAACAUGAAUCUGGAGAUUCUUCUGGGUGUAUAAAACCCCCUAAAUCACCACUUUCCCCAGAAUUAAUACAAGUCGAGGAUUUGACGCUUGUAUCUCAGCUUUCUUCUUCAGUGAUAAAUAAAACUAGUCCUCCACAGCCUGUGAAUCCCCCUAGACCUUUCAAGCAUAGUGAGCGGAGAAGAAGAUCUCAGCGUUUAGCCACCUUACCCAUGCCUGAUGAUUCUGUAGAAAAGGUUUCUUCUCCCUCUCCAGCCACUGAUGGGAAAGUAUUCUCCAUCAGUUCUCAAAAUCAGCAAGAAUCUUCAGUACCAGAGGUGCCUGAUGUUGCACAUUUGCCACUUGAGAAGCUGGGACCCUGUCUCCCUCUUGACUUAAGUCGUGGUUCAGAAGUUACAGCACCGGUAGCCUCAGAUUCCUCUUACCGUAAUGAAUGUCCCAGGGCAGAAAAAGAGGAUACACAGAUGCUUCCAAAUCCUUCUUCCAAAGCAAUAGCUGAUGGAAGAGGAGCUCCAGCAGCAGCAGGAAUAUCGAAAACAGAAAAAAAAGUGAAAUUGGAAGACAAAAGCUCAACAGCAUUUGGUAAGAGAAAAGAAAAAGAUAAGGAAAGAAGAGAGAAGAGAGACAAAGAUCACUACAGACCAAAACAGAAGAAGAAGAAAAAAAAGAAAAAGAAAUCUAAGCAACAUGACUAUUCAGACUAUGAAGACAGUUCCCUCGAAUUUUUGGAAAGGUGCUCUUCUCCACUAACUCGAUCUUCUGGGAGUUCUCUGGCUUCACGAAGCAUGUUUACGGAGAAAACUACAACCUAUCAGUACCCAAGGGCAAUUCUAUCCGUUGAUCUUAGUGGUGAAAACUUAUCAGAUGUAGACUUCCUAGAUGAUUCUUCAACGGAGAGUUUGCUUCUGAGUGGGGAUGAAUACAAUCAGGACUUUGAUUCAACCAAUUUUGAGGAAUCUCAGGAUGAGGAUGAUGCUCUUAAUGAAAUUGUGCGAUGUAUUUGUGAGAUGGAUGAGGAGAAUGGCUUCAUGAUCCAGUGUGAAGAGUGCUUGUGUUGGCAACACAGCGUGUGCAUGGGGCUGCUGGAGGAGAGCAUUCCAGAGCAGUACAUCUGCUAUAUCUGCCGGGACCCACCAGGUCAGAGGUGGAGUGCAAAAUAUCGUUAUGAUAAGGAGUGGUUGAAUAAUGGGAGAAUGUGCGGGUUAUCAUUUUUCAAAGAAAAUUAUUCUCAUCUCAAUGCCAAAAAGAUAGUUUCUACACAUCACCUGCUUGCUGAUGUCUAUGGUGUUACAGAAGUGCUACACGGGCUACAGCUGAAGAUUGGAAUACUAAAGAAUAAACAUCAUCCUGACCUUCAUCUCUGGGCUUGUUCCGGGAAGCGAAAAGACCAAGAUCAAAUAAUAGCUGGGGUGGAGAAAAAAAUAGCUCAAGACACAGUUAAUCGAGAAGAAAAGAAAUAUGUACAGAACCAUAAAGAACCACCUCGUUUGCCCCUAAAAAUGGAAGGAACUUAUAUAACAAGUGAGCAUAGCUAUCAAAAGCCACAAAGUUUUGGUCAGGACUGUAAAUCUCUCGCAGACCCUGGGAGCUCAGAUGAUGAUGAUGUUAGUAGUUUGGAAGAAGAACAAGAAUUCCACAUGAGAAGUAAAAACAGUUUACAGUACUCAGCAAAAGAACAUGGAAUGCCUGAAAAGAAGAAUCCAGCUGAAGGGAAUACAGUAUUUGUUUAUAAUGAUAAAAAGGGCACCGAAGACCCAGGAGACUCACAUCUUCAGUGGCAGCUCAAUCUCCUUACACACAUAGAAAAUGUGCAGAACGAAGUUACCAGCAGGAUGGACCUAAUAGAAAAAGAAGUCGAUGUUCUGGAAAGCUGGCUUGAUUUCACAGGGGAGUUGGAGCCACCAGAUCCUCUUGCAAGAUUGCCCCAACUUAAACGCCACAUAAAACAGCUCCUAAUUGACAUGGGCAAAGUACAGCAGAUAGCAACUCUUUGCUCUGUAUGACAACAGUGAACACUUAAUGAAAGAAUGUGGCUUUCUUCAGUCAAAGCAUUUUUAUUAUCCACGUGAUGGCUAAGUGGAUAAUUUAAAAGCUUAGUAAUGUCUGGUCAUUCACUGAUUUGUGAUGUCAAUAGGAUGGCACCUUGGAAAGAAAAAUGAAGAACAACUUUAUCAAGGAAGCUAGUAUUUAAAAACAAAUUCAUGAGCAAGCUGCAAAUGAGAAUGUGUUAUAUGCCAAGGAACAAUGAAGUAGAAUAUAAUGUAUACUAAGGGAUUUCAAGUUCUCAGAAUUUUUGAGUAGUUGCUUACGUGAAGCUCAAGAUACCUGUAGAAAGAAAUAUGGUAUAUUUGUAUAGUUUUUAAUAGAAAGAUCUAUGUUUAUAAACCAGCACUUGGCCAAAAACAAAAUUGUAAAGGAAAUUUAAAUUCUGGAGAAUUCUACAGGGUUGCUCUAAGAACUGUCUUCUCAGCAGUUGAUCCAGCUGUACGGAAAUUUAGGGUAUUUAAACUUUUAAAGGAUCAUGAGCUGUUUCUUGGGCGAUGAAUGUUCUCAAUCAGAAAACUGACAGUAGAAAUCUCACUUCUGGGGAAAACAGUUGUGGAAUUCUUACUUCAUUAUGAAUGUAUUUAAAAAACAAACACCAAAUAAUUGGAAUAUAUUGCAGGCAUUAAGCUCAUUAAAAACAAACUGGCUUGCAGAAGGGUCCGAUGUGCCAAGUGAUCAUGAUUCUGCUGGAAAGAGGAUUUUAAAUAUUGUGGGAGUUCUCCCACCCUAAGUCUUACAUAAUGCCACCAGUCCAUCCAAAACCUAUAUAUCACCUAUACUAUAUAUAUCAUAUAUAUAGUUGAAUGGCAGUAUUCAGGCUCAACGUACAGUUUGAUCCUGAGUAUGCUUGGUGUUUGCCUUCAGAAAAAAAAAAAUACAUUGUAAAUAACCUCAGCUGGGAUGAGGAGUGACAGAAUAUCAAAAUAAUUUGUGGCUGUGGAUUUUUUUAACUGCUAGUAGUGGAAUACUGGAAAAGCUUCAUUUCUGAAGAUGAAUUUUAUUUUUAAAAAAUACAUGCACACUCAAAACUUUUAGCUUUGAUCACAAGUGGACAAAUUUCUGAAACCAAAGGCAACUAAGUUGCUGUGUUAGCUCUUGCUGGAUUUUGAGCCUAGGUCCUACUGUCUGCCAGUACUCAUGUGAGUUGUAUGUGCCCCCAGUGCUACAUACGCAGGUAUGCGUAAGUGUGUAUGCUUGUUUUAAACAAACACUCAACGUACAUAUGUACAUAAUCUACACAUAUUUAUAUCACAUAUCUAGUUUUAUUACUAUAGACUAUACGAAUUGGUGGUUAACAUGAAAUGUUACCUUUUAACAGACUGUUUUUAAAAAUUAAAAAUGUAUGUAUAGGUUUUGAAAUUUUUUUAAAAGGGGAGAAAGACUGUUAAGAGGAGGCUAUUUGAUGACAUAACACUUGAAUAUUUUAUGCCUCAUUCUGUUUAUCAGUUCUCGCAAUCUGUAUAAAUGCAUUUUAGAACUGAUAGACAGUAAACUUGAAUUUAUCUUUGAUAAGAAUACAUGCCACUGUACAUUCAGAUAUUAUUUAAAUUUGCAAACACAUUGUUCUAUAUGUAAGGGUACUGUAUGUAAAACUCUGUAUUAAAACUAUUCCACAUAUCCUAAAAUUUCAGCUUGCCUUUUUGCGGCCUUAUAUUUUGAUGUAAAGAUUAAAAGAAUGUGCAAAACAGUCAGAAAUUUUUAUUGCCUUUUGAGAUUCUCCAACUUGACAAAUGUGCCAAAGAUCAACAGACAGAAAAUAUCAUCCUGUGUAUUUACUUGUCAUACUUUAACUUUGUGAAAGAUCUUACUGAUAAAUGAAAAGCUUUAGCAGAGGUGGUAUUGUGGGGUAAUUGCUUAAAUUUACAUAUCAAAGUAAAAAAGUAGUGCCUGUAUUCCAUGUGUGGAGUAAAUUUGCUAAUGUCUAUAUUUUAUGAUUGAUACUAUUAUUUUUCCUUUGCAUUUUAAAAUAGUGGCUCUAAUAUUUUCCCUGUCAUGGCUACAUUCUAGACAUUGAAUUUAUAUCUUCUUUUUUUCAGAUACGGAGCAAAUAGCAUCCUUAACCUAUGAAUAAUGGUGUUGCCUAGAUUCUUGUCACACACACAGAAGACCCUUUGUACCUAGUAACAUUCAUCCUCUUGAUUCCUGGUGAACACGGUUAAAUUCAUGCACAUUUGUUCUUGUAGUUUCUAAAAAUUAGAUCAAUUUAUUUGUUAGCCAGCAAAUUGAAAAUUCCAUUAUUAGAUUAAUGAAAUUUUUGCUCUGCUUAUAUGUAUACGAACUGGAAAUCUGAAUUUUUAAAUUUAGAUCUUUAAAUCAAAUUAUUUUUAUGCAUAUUUUCAUUUAAUAUAGAGUAUACCAAUCGAUUGAAGCCUUUCACAAGUAGUGCGCUGAGCUUUUCUUAUUGAAGAGAGUGAAUUAGUUUCUGAGAAGUCAGUCUAUUGUGAAAAGUUUCAGAUGAGAUUAUUUUCUUUUAGUCUUUUUAAAUAUCACUAUAUGUAUUUAAAUAGAAGCAAUAAACUAGAGAGAGUGUUUCUUGAAAAGACAAUGUUUUAUUUGCCACCAGGCAGAACAGAAUGAGCAUUGGUAGAGAAGGCUCCCUCUUGGUAUGUUACUGAUAAACUUGUACUUCCUCAUACUUGUUUGUGGUUCUACUGACUUAUUUCCAAACUUAAGAGUAAUGUACUUCGAAAACAACUUGGUUAUUCUUUAAAUUUCAGGUAAAACCCCUUUUCCUAACACUCAUCUUAUUUCCACUGUCUUAUUUCCUCUCAGAUGUUCAUAUUUCACAUGUUCAAAAUGAAGCGUACUAUUUCCCCUCCAAUAAACGAAGUCUCCUGCCAA